AGCAUUCUUUUGGACACCACACCUAGGUCGGAGCACUGUCGUCCUUCAGGGCUCCAGCCUCUUGAUAUUUUUGUACUUCAGUAUCAGCUCGAUAGAGCAAAAGAGAGAGAGGACGAGAGAGGGGGGUGAGGAGAAAAGAGAGAGAGCGCGAGAGGGAGAGGGAGAGAAGGAGGGGUGGGAAUUACACAAAGAGAGAACCAAAAAUAAUUUUGAUUCCUAAGUUAAUUUGCUCACUGAUCUGGGAUUUUAGUCACCAUGGAGGGUAAAUGGACAAUCUGCCCAGGACUGCAGCCCGAUACUAUUUUUCAAAGCCAGAACUUACUCCAUUUUCUAUGCAAAUGUCAGAAAAAUGAAACACCCUCUCUCCCAAGUCAGAGAAGGGGAAGCAACGGCUCUCACGUUGGGACAAUAUUAUCUGGAAGCUGAAGAAGAAACUGAAUACUCCUUCCUUCCUCCCCACCCAUUCCUUUAAAUCCGGAGGGGGAAAAAAUCCCAAGGUCUGCAAAGGGCCUGGAAUCUCCGCCGAGGCCGGCGAGGGAGAGGAAACGGCUAGAGAAACACAGAAAAGACAAUUUACAGAGAAAUGUUUACUAUCUCCCUUCGGAGACAUUUUUGAAAUUAAAGGGCUGUGGGUGGAAACACCAAAAAUGAGGGAGACUCCCCCCUCACCAGGAAGCCUGCCCGAGAAUGCCCAAGUAUCUCGCCACUCCCGCAGGAGGGAGCCUCGCUCUACAGGGAGACAGUUUUGUGGUUUUAAUGCGGCGCGGCGCUCGGACUAUAAAACACAACAAAUCAUAAACCCGGCGGAGCAGCAGCGGCCGCGCGCGCCUCCCCUCCCAAUGAGUUCCUAUUUCGUGAACUCCACCUUCCCCGUCACUCUGGCCAGCGGGCAGGAGUCCUUCCUGGGCCAGCUACCGCUCUAUUCGUCGGGCUAUGCGGACCCGCUGAGACAUUACCCCGCGCCCUACGGGCCAGGGCCGGGCCAGGACAAGGGCUUUGCCACUUCCUCCUAUUACCCGCCGGCGGGCGGUGGCUACGGCCGAGCGGCGCCCUGCGACUACGGGCCGGCGCCGGCCUUCUACCGCGAGAAAGAGUCGGCCUGCGCACUCUCCGGCGCCGACGAGCAGCCCCCGUUCCACCCCGAGCCGCGGAAGUCGGACUGCGCGCAGGACAAGAGCGUGUUCGGCGAGACAGAAGAGCAGAAGUGCUCCACUCCGGUCUACCCGUGGAUGCAGCGGAUGAAUUCGUGCAACAGUUCCUCCUUUGGGCCCAGCGGCCGGCGAGGCCGCCAGACAUACACACGUUACCAGACGCUGGAGCUGGAGAAGGAGUUUCACUACAAUCGCUACCUGACGCGGCGGCGGCGCAUCGAGAUCGCGCACGCCCUGUGCCUGACGGAGAGGCAGAUCAAGAUAUGGUUCCAGAACCGACGCAUGAAGUGGAAAAAGGAGAGCAAACUGCUCAGCGCGUCUCAGCUCAGUGCCGAGGAGGAGGAAGAAAAACAGGCCGAGUGAAGGUGCUGGAAAGGGAGGGAGGACGCGAGGGGAAAGGCCUGUGGGGAGCCGAGGGCGUCAGAGAGACCCGGGAAGGAAGGCUCUCGGGUGGGGGAGCCAGGAGACCUGCUCUCCGGCGCAGACAGGCGGGGCCCAGCGCUCUCCUGGACGCCCCCGCCCGCACAGCUCCCGGCGGGUGCUCUGAGGCCUCACUACUCGAGCCCACCCAGCAUCCCGCGCGCCCUUCCUUCCCGAGGAACUCGCCUCAGCCUGAUCAGGCUUCCUGGUGAGAACUGAGGAGCGGACUCACUUGAUGUUUCCUGGAAGCAGAGCAAAAUGCUCUUGUCCCUGUCGCGUCUCAUUUUGUCCAUGUCCCCCGUGCACGGUUCAAUGGUAGAUUCGCUGUCCCCUCAGCGGGGGCCUUGAAGACUCCCUGAUCCCAGACCUGUCGUCUCUCCCACCCCCUCCCCAAAGCCACUGGAAGGAGCACAUACUACCUAGAAGUAAGAAGAGGAGCCUCAGAAGAAAACAAAGUUCUAUUUUAUUAAUUUUCUAUGUGUUGUGUUUGUAGUCUUGUCUUAGCUCUGGACGUGAAAUACUUCGAUGAUGAUGAUGAUGAUGAUGAUGAUAAUAAUAAUAAUAAUAACAACAACAACAACAAUAAUAAAGAUGUGAAAACUCGA